GAGGGGGUAAAUAUUCCAGUGGAUACAAGCUUGGACUCUUUUCUUGAAGCUUUCUUUCUAUCAGAAGCAUUUGCUGAUAUUGCUGACAUUGAAACAUUAAAAGAAAAUUUGAGAAGCAAUGGGCAUCCUGAAGCUGCAAGUAUUUCUCAUUGUGCUCUCUGUUGCAUUGAACCAUCUGAAAGCUACACCCAUUGAAAGUCAUCAGGUGGAAAAGCGGAAAUGCAACACUGCCACAUGUGCAACGCAGCGCCUGGCAAAUUUUUUAGUUCAUUCCAGCAACAACUUUGGUGCCAUUCUCUCAUCUACCAACGUGGGAUCCAAUACAUAUGGCAAGAGGAAUGCAGUAGAGGUUUUAAAGAGAGAGCCACUGAAUUACUUGCCCCUUUAGAGGACAAUGUAACUCUAUAGUUAUUGUUUUAUGUUCUAGUGAUUUCCUGUAUAAUUUAACAGUGCCCUUUUCAUCUCCAGUGUGAAUAUAUGGUCUGUGUGUCUGAUGUUUGUUGCUAGGACAUAUACCUUCUCAAAAGAUUGUUUUAUAUGUAGUACUAACUAAGGUCCCAUAAUAAAAAGAUAGUAUCUUUUAAAAUGAAAUGUUUUUGCUAUAGAUUUGUAUUUUAAAACAUAAGAACGUCAUUUUGGGACCUAUAUCUCAGUGGCACAGGUUUAAGAACGAAGGAGAAAAAGGUAGUUUGAACCUUGGUAAAUUGUAAACAGCUAAUAAUGAAGUUAUUCUUGACAUGAGAAAAUCAGUAAUUGGACCAGGCGCGGUGGCUCUUGCCUGUAAUCCCAGCACUUUGGGAGGCCGAGGCAGGCAGAUCACAAGGUCAGGAGUUCGAGACCAGCCUGACCAACAUGGUGAAACCCUGUCUCUACUAAAAAUACAAAAAUUAGCCGGGGGUGGUGACAUGUGCCUGUAAUCCCAGCUACUCAGGAGGCUAAGGCAGGAGAAUCGCUUAAACCCAGGAGGCGGAGGUUGCAGUGAGCCGAGAUUGCACCACUGCACUCCAGCCUGGGUGGCAGAGUGAGACUCGUCUCAAAAAAAAGAAAGAAAAUUAGUAAUUGUAAGUACCCCUGAUAAGCAAAUUAGUAAUUGUCAAUACCCCUGUUAAGCAAUUCCUUUUUGCAGUAUAUUUCUGAAAUGACAGAAUGCUGUUUUAAAAACAAAGAAAUAAAAUCCUGCUCCUGACUCGGUCAAAAUAUUUUUUAAAGUCUAUUGUUUGUUGUGCUUGCUGGUACUAAGAGGCUAUUUAAAAGUAUAAAACUGCUUUGUAUCCAUGAGGGUUUCAUUGUGUGUUAGCAGCAGUGAGCUUCUAUUAAAUGUAUAUGUCAUUUAUUUUGUUUAAGUGGCUUUCAGCAAACCUCAGUCAUAUUCUUAUGCAGGGUAUUGCGAAACAACUUGUGUUCUAUUAAUCGUGUCUUCAAUUAAAAGACCACAGACUUCUGGAAACUCUUUGCUGUAUAAGAAUUAUUUCUUUUGUUUAACAAAUUAGACAUUUCUGGCAGAGGUUAUGUAUAUGAUACACUUUUUUUGAUAGCAGCUGCAAUGUUGGACAGAAGAUGAAAUGCUUUGCUUUGAGUCAGAUUCUUAUGAAUAUCUGCUUUUCCCUGACUUUGAGUUAGGUAGCUUUGGAAGUAGCAUUAAUUCAGAUAAACUGCCAUCAUGCUGCGUUAUGCCAUUUCUAAAGACACUCAACUUGUACUUUUAAAAAAAUAGAAAAAAUAAGCAUUUCAAUCUAAGUGGAAAUUUGACUCAUUGACUUACAUUUCUAAGUUAAAAUUUCCCUUUAUGAAGUGUGCCUUAGGUUACCAAAUUGUAGAGGCUUUCGUUGGUGGUGGUAAGUGGUAGCGGUAGUGAGUGUAUAGAGGCAGGGAAAUAUAUUUAUAAUAAAUUCUAUGUCAUGAAUUACAUAUUGAAAUAAAUAGGUGAAUAUACAAAUUUAUA